GCUCGCGGAAACCGGAAGCGGCGGCUGUCCGCGGUGCCGGCUGGGGGCGGAGAGGCGGCGGUGGGCUCCCUGGGGUGUGUGAGCCCGGUGAUGGAGCCGGGCCCGACAGCCGCGCAGCGGAGGUGUUCGUUGCCGCCGUGGCUGCCGCUGGGGCUGCUGCUGUGGUCGGGGCUGGCCCUGGGCGCGCUCCCCUUCGGCAGCAGUCCGCACAGGGUCUUCCACGACCUCCUGUCGGAGCAGCAGUUGCUGGAGGUGGAGGACUUGUCCCUGUCCCUCCUGCAGGGUGGAGGGCUGGGGCCUCUGUCGCUGCCCCCGGACCUGCCGGAUCUGGAUCCUGAGUGCCGGGAGCUCCUGCUGGACUUCGCCAACAGCAGCGCAGAGCUGACAGGGUGUCUGGUGCGCAGCGCCCGGCCCGUGCGCCUCUGUCAGACCUGCUACCCCCUCUUCCAACAGGUCGUCAGCAAGAUGGACAACAUCAGCCGAGCCGCGGGGAAUACUUCAGAGAGUCAGAGUUGUGCCAGAAGUCUCUUAAUGGCAGAUAGAAUGCAAAUAGUUGUGAUUCUCUCAGAAUUUUUUAAUACCACAUGGCAGGAGGCAAAUUGUGCAAAUUGUUUAACAAACAACAGUGAAGAAUUAUCAAACAGCACAGUAUAUUUCCUUAAUCUAUUUAAUCACACCCUGACCUGCUUUGAACAUAACCUUCAGGGGAAUGCACAUAGUCUUUUACAGACAAAAAAUUAUUCAGAAGUAUGCAAAAACUGCCGUGAAGCAUACAAAACUCUGAGUAGUCUGUACAGUGAAAUGCAAAAAAUGAAUGAACUUGAGAAUAAGGCUGAACCUGGAACACAUUUAUGCAUUGAUGUGGAAGAUGCAAUGAACAUCACUCGAAAACUAUGGAGUCGAACUUUCAACUGUUCAGUCCCUUGCAGUGACACAGUGCCUGUAAUUGCUGUUUCUGUGUUCAUUCUCUUUCUACCUGUUGUCUUCUACCUUAGUAGCUUUCUUCACUCAGAGCAAAAGAAACGCAAACUCAUUCUGCCCAAACGUCUCAAGUCCAGUACCAGUUUUGCAAAUAUUCAGGAAAAUUCAAACUGAGACCUACAAAAUGGAGAAUUGACAUAUCACGUGAAUGAAUGGUGGAAGACACAACUUGGUUUCAGAAAGAAGAUAAACUGUGAUUUGACAAGUCAAGCUCUUAAGAAAUACAAGGACUUCAGAUCCAUUUUUAAAUAAGAAUUUUCGAUUUUUCUUUCCUUUUCCACUUCUUUCUAACAGAUUUGGAUAUUUUUAAUUUCCAGGCAUAGCAAUGUUAUCUAUUUUAAUGUGUAUUUGUCACAAUAACAGAACAUGCAAGAACAAUCAUUAUUUUAUUUUAUAGGCAUUUGAUUACUAUUCUAGACUUCUGGUAUCUUCUUACUAACAUAAAUAUCUCAAGUAGAAAAGUUUUUGAAAACUAACAUUUAAAAAUUAAUCAGUUACAGUAAAGACUUUGAAAAAGAAAUGUACUUGUUAGGAAGUAGCUUAAUUACCCCCCAUUGCAGUAUUAUUGUUAUAUAUAUAGUUAAUAUGUUGUACAUCACAAUAAUAUAUAAUUCAGUCUCUAGUUUCCCUAGAGUCAUUUUUGAAACCACUGAUUGCAAACCUCCCUGACAAUUUUUAAAAGUAGUAAGCCACAUUACAUUUAUCUUUGUAAAAAGAUUUAUGGUAACUGGUUUCUUACUUGACUUUUAUAAAUAGUAUUUUACAUCUUAUUUUUGCCUUUAUUUCAUAAGUAAUUUAAAAAUCACUGGAUUGCUUUAUUAUAUUCAGGGCAAUAUGGAUUAUUUUUAUACCAAGGAUUUGCAUCGUGAAUUACAUUAAGUUAUUUGGCAAUUUAUAAUUUAUUACUACUUUAAAUCAAAUGUAGCAUUAUCACACUGUAUUUAAAUUGUCAUUUUUUAAAGGAAUAUUUUCUUCUUAAGAUAUAUAGAGGAUUUUGGAGAAGAGAGACAGGAGGGGUAAAACCAGCUUAAGGUUCAGCGAGCAGAAAGGGACCUGAGAGGAUGCUCACUGUAAGACUGUUGGACAGUGGUGUGUAUUGAGGGGAUGAAUCGGAACGAUAGUCUCAUGCAGAAAAUAGUGAGAUUAAGAUCAUCCUUAUUGUUUCUAAAUUAUUUCAAUCAGAUGAAAGUGAUACGAUUGAAAUGAAAUCACAUAGUUCGUGCUCAGAAAUUCUAUUUUGGUAUGUUUGUAUUAGCCUUUAGAAAAAACACUCCGUUUCAGAAUUGUUCACAGUUUUAUUUCUUAGGUUUUUAGAGUUCAGGAUUUCAUUUAUUAAUUUCUUCUUGCUUUUUUGGUGGAAAUAGGCUUUGUUGUAAACAUUAAGAAUAUAAAAUCUCCUCUAUAUAGAAACAAGAAUUUUGUUAAAAAGAGAAUUUGAAUCCCUUCCUAUACUAUAAAAUGCUCUAUAGGGAGACAAAGUGUUUCUUUUUUCUUUUAUGUUUACUGUUUAUGUGGAGUGAAAUAUAAGGCUCUUGGAUGUAUAACAUACUCAAAAGCUGUUACACUUUCUCUGAUCUGCUGUGAUCCACUGAAAAUGUGCUGGGGUUUGUUCUGCUGUCACUGUUUAUGCUGCUGGAACUUAGCACUGUCUUGAUUUGAAGCAUAUGAUUGAGAGCCAUUUGAAGCAAUCUUCAUUAAUGCAGAUAAAACAAGUUUACAUGUGCAGAGUUAGAAAAUGACAUGUUCAAUUCUGUAAGUGGUGACUUUUUGAGCACCUUUCAGUAUUAUGUAUUUGUAAAAACCAUUGUUUUUGGAUAUAAAGCUAAUAAGCACUUUAAAAAGGAAAAGGCAGCCUUUACUAUUUUUUCUGGUUGAGUCAUUGCUCUUUAGACCUAGCAUCAGCAAUAGAUUUCAAAGAUAAGUAUUAAGCGCUACCCUAAAGUGUGUAAGUUUUUCAUUUUGUCAUAUUGAAAAAUGAUUUGCAUAGUACUGAAUGUUGACACACAGCUUAUAUGUAUUUACAAGAAUAUCUUUAAGUGUUUUUUUGACACAUUAAAAUAAAGGAAAUAAGGAAAUUGUAAGCUUUAUUUGGAUUUUUAAAUACAUUUUUAAAAUUUCAGAUGUAAUUUAACAUCACAUUUGUUUUUCAGGUAUUGAGUUUAGAUGCCUACUUUUAUGAGUACCAUCAGCUGGACACAGUGUCUCAUACCUGUAUUUGCAGCACUUUGGGAGGCUGAAGCAGAUCGCUGGAGCUUAUGAGUUCGAGACCAGCCUGGACAACAUAGUGAAACACUGUCUCUGCAAAAAAUACAAAAAUUAGCUGGGUAUGGUGGUAAGUGCCUGUAGUCCUAGCUACUUGGGAGGCUGAGAUGGGAGGAUGUCUUGAGCCCGGGAGGUGGAGGUUGCAAUGAGCCAAGAUUGUACCACUGCAUUCCAACCUGGGCGACAGAGCCAGACCUUGUCUCAAAAAAAAAAAAAAAAAAAGAAAAAAGAAAGUACUGUCUGUCUUAAAUUUUGCUGCAAAUAAAAAUGUACUUUGGAUUAUUUAUUGUUGAACUUGAGAGAUAGAAAUAACAUCAGAUAUAUUUUUUCUUUUUUUUUUAUAAUUAAUUUUUUUUUUUUUUUUUUUUGUAGAGACAGUGUCUCACUAUGUUGCCCAAGCUGGUCUUGAACUCCUGAGUUCAAGAGAUCCUCCUGCCUUAGCCUCCCAAAGUGCUGGGAUUACAAGCAUAAGCACCACACCUGGCUGAACAUCAGAUAUUUUAAAGUGUAGCCCAGAGUCUAGUUGGUAAAUGUUACUUAUAUUGGGACUAGUAUUUUCUAAUGUUUCUGGGAUAUGCUCCCUAUAAAAUGAAAUGUUUUCCUGGAACAAUGCUAAUUAGGAUUGCAUUCCUGGCCAAAGACAUGACAUCAAAUAAGUAAUAGACAUCACCAGCAAUGAAUUUUGAAAAGCAAAAAAUACUAUUAACCUAUAUAACCAUUUAAAAUUUAAAAAAUUAUGUUCCAAGUACCUCUAUUUUCUGAGCUAGAAGAAACCUUAGAGGCCAUCUGAUGAUAGAUUCCCAGAGCUGGAUGGAUCCCUAGGGACUACCUAAUCUGACUUUCUGUCCACUGCAUGGAUUCUUCUAAAAAGUAUGUCACUUAUUUCCCUACCUUAUUAAGACUAAAUAAGUGGAACAUCAUAGAGCUCUUUAUUUAUAACAGUCAUUCUUUGAUAGUCAACUCUUAAAUGGAGACUUGAGAUGCUUAAAUAUUGUACUACUGUGCUUAUCUUGUAAAGAUUUCAUAAAAUGAUAGUAUUGGUUAUUUUAAAAAGGCUUUGGCUUAUGCUGAAUUAUACAUGUAGCACCAAAAUGUUACAACUCUACUAAAUUUCCUUGUUCUAAACUAUUAUAUUAGCUAUAAUAAAUAUUAGUCAUACAUGUAACAUGUUUAAUGACAAAUAACUUUCUUUAUCUCCUUGGAAUUAAAGAGGGCUUUUAAAAGAUAA